GUUGUGAGUAGUCGUCUCUGAGGCUCUGGUGGCACAGUUGCAGCUUUGGAGCUAAGCAUGGCCUUCUCUCAGCUCCUUGGCCUACUGCCGUGGCCUUGGUGCCCCCCUCCUCUGGUGGUCAGCUCAGGGCUUCCUCUGCCCAUGCAGUCCCCAGCUGCCACUGCUGAGGGCCUCAGUGGCCCCCUCUUUGGGGCCUACACGUUCCCCACCUUCAAGUUUCAGCCUCGCCAUGAUAGCAUGGACUGGAGACGCAUUAGCACCCUGGAUGUAGACCGCGUGGCCCGGGAACUGGAUGUGGCCACUCUGCAGGAGAAUAUUGCUGGCAUCACCUUCUGCAACUUGGACCGGGAGGUGUGCAGCCGCUGUGGGCAGCCUGUGGACCCGGCACUGCUCAAGGUGCUGCGCCUGGCGCAGCUCAUCAUUGAGUACCUGCUGCACUGCCAGGAUUGCCUGAGUGCCAGUGUUGCCCAGCUGGAGGCACGGCUGCAGACCAGCCUGGGCCAGCAGCAGCGUGGUCAGCAGGAGCUGGGACGCCAGGCUGACGAGCUCAAGGGUGUGCGGGAGGAGAGCCGCCGGCGUCGCAAGAUGAUCAGCACCCUGCAGCAGCUGCUAAUGCAGACAGGCACCCACAGCUACCACACGUGCCACCUGUGUGACAAGACAUUCAUGAAUGCCACCUUUCUCCGGGGCCACAUCCAGCGCAGGCAUGCAGGCGUGGCAGAAGGUGGAAAACAGAAGAAACAGGAACAGCCAGUGGAAGAGGUGUUAGAAGAGCUACGGGCCAAGCUAAAGUGGACCCAAGGGGAGCUGGAAGCCCAGAGGGAGGCGGAGAGGCAGCGGCAGCUCCAGGAAGCAGAGCUCAUUCAUCAGAGGGAAAUAGAAGCUAAGAAAGAAUUUGAUAAAUGGAAAGAGCAAGAGUGGACCAAACUUUAUGGGGAAAUAGAUAAACUAAAAAAAUUAUUUUGGGAUGAAUUUAAAAAUGUCGCCAAGCAGAACUCUACACUAGAAGAGAAACUGCGGGCACUGCAGUCCCACAGUGUGAUGGAGUCCAAGCUGGGAUCACUGCGAGAUGAGGAGUCAGAGGAGUGGCUUCGGCAGGCACGGGAGCUUCAGGCCCUGAGAGAGAAGACAGAAAUUCAGAAAACGGAGUGGAAAAGAAAAGUGAAGGAACUGCAUGAAGAGCACAUGGCUGAGAAGAAAGAGCUACAGGAGGAGAACCAGAGGCUCCAGGCCUCCCUGUCUCAGGAUCAGAAGAAGGCAGCUGCCCAGUCCCAGUGCCAGAUCAGCACCCUCCGUGCCCAGCUGCAGGAACAAGCUAGGAUCAUUGCCUCCCAGGAGGAGAUGAUCCAGUCCUUGUCUCUCAGGAAGGUGGAAGGGAUCCACAAGGUGCCAAAGGCUGUGGACACAGAGGAGGACUCUCCAGAGGAAGAGAUGGAGGACUCCCAGGAUGAACAGCACAAGGUGCUGGCAGCUCUGAGGCGUAACCCCACUUUGCUGAAGCACUUCAGACCAAUCCUGGAGGACACCCUGGAAGAGAAGCUCGAAAGCAUGGGGAUAAGGAAGGAUGCAAAGGGAAUCUCGAUUCAGACUCUCAGACACCUGGAAUCCCUGCUGAGAGUCCAGCGGGAGCAGAAGGCCCGGAAGUUUUCUGAAUUUCUGAGUCUGAGGGGAAAGCUUGUCAAGGAAGUCACCAGCAGAGCGAAGGAGAGACAGGAGAAUGGCGCUGUGGUGUCCCAGCCAGACGGGCAGCCUUCAGAAGAAAAUAAGACUAACAUAGCAAUCCUGUGAGCUCAUGGAAAUUAUUACUUGGACAAGUAUCAAGCAGGUAUUUUGUGCUUAAAAGCAUUGUCAUUUUGGCAUGAAAAUAUGGUAAAAAAAUGUAUUGAUGACCUGGGAAACUAUAAUAUUUAGUUUAAACUUCUGGCCUUAAAAUCUCUAAGGAAAGGACGGUUUUUAUCUUGCAUAGAAAUCUCAGACAGAAGGGUAUUUGUCCUGGUUGCCAAUCUGCCUUUUAUGCUCCAAUUUAAACGUAUAUCCUUUUGCUCAUUCAGUCAAAUGUUCAUUCAUUCAUUUGCCCACUCAUUCAUUUAGUACAGUACUUGCUGAGGUUGACUCUGUGCCAGGGCCUUCCACCUCACCUGGGAAAUCAGCCAGGACCAGGUGAUGUGAUGGAGCCAAGCAUGGGGGUGGUGGGAGCUCAGAGGAGGGAGGGGACAGGGACUUGGGGAGGAUGAAUGGAAAAACCCUCGGAAUGCUGGCUUCCAAGAGAAAGCAAAGGUAUCUUGCUCCUUCUAGGUGCUACGCCCCACCCACUCCCACACACCUUUGUUCCUGUAGUAAAAAAGCCAGGAGGGAGAGCCCCCUUCGCAGCCUUCCCUUUCCCUGGCCCUGGGGUUCUGCCUUCUCUGGAGAUGUUACUGAGUUGUGAGAUGAGCGCUGUGUUUUUGUGGCAUUUUGUAGACCUUUCCUUCCAGCUCUGCACCUUUAUUCUUUUCCUGGGUCCCACAAGUGCUGUCUUAAUGCUCACCUCCCAUUUCUGCUUGGACCCUGCCUCUUCUGUGGCCUGGGCAAGGCUGUGGGAAGUAGCGGUGAGGGCCCAAGAUUAGGGCAGACAGACAACCUGGGUUUGUAUUCACCACUUUCUUCCGUGGAGCUGAGGGCAAGCCUCUGUAGGGAAAAUGAUAGCCUCUGAAGAUGCUCGGGGGCCAAGUGGUUGUAUGUAAAGUGCUUUUCUUAGUAUCUGGUACACAGUCAUGGGAAGCUAUUGUUAUUUUCCCCCAGCAGGCUUGUCUUUGUCUUCCCCUUCUCUUCAGUUCACUCUUUCCUGGAAGCUCCACUUCUGAGUAGACACAUUCACUGAGAGCAGUGCAUAGCUGGCCCUUGAACAAUGCAGGGGUCAGGGGCGCAAACCCCCCAUGCAGUUGAAAAUUUGCGUGUAACUUUUGACUGCCCCAAAACUUAACUACUCAUAGCCUACUGUUGACCAGAAGUCUUACCGACAAUAUGGACUAUUAACACACAUUUUGUAUGUUAUAUGAAUUAUAAGCUGUAUUAUUACAAUAAAGUAAGCUAGAGAAAAGAACAUGUUAUUAAGAAAAUCACAAGGAAGAGCAAAUAUGUUUACUAUUCAUUAAGGGGAAGUGGAUCAUCAUAAAGGACUUCAUCCUUGUUAUCUUUGUGUUGAGUAGGCUGAAGAGGAGGAGGAAGAGGAGGGGUUGCUCUUGCUGUCUCACGGGUGGCAGAGUCGGAAGAAAAUCCACGUAUAAGUGGACCCAUGGCUGUUCAACCCCACGUUGUUUCGGGGUCAACUGUAUUUCAAACAUUUUCUGAUCUUGAAUUACUGUAAGAAACUCAUUUUACAUUGUGACCCAAUCCACACAUGUCUGACUCCCUGUGAUGCACUCUCUCUCUUCUCUUCCCAUAAAAACUUGCUGAUCCGGGACCGCUCUUGUGGCUAUAGGUCUUGAUGCAAUUUGGAAAACAGAGGGGCUGUGUCCAAUUGCCUGCCUUGGUACUGCCUUGCCCCAGACUGCAUUUGGGAGGAGGUUUGAGUGGAUCUUGAUGGUUCAUGCAGUCCUGCGGCGACCUCUGGUGGCAGUGGGGUCUUCCUGCAGGACUGCCUGCAGUGCAGCGGCUGUAGCGUGGGUUGGGGAGAGGGUAGCAGCCUUGGUGAAGUCCAUCUAGGACUACUGAGCCCCUCUUCAGGCCCGCGGACUCCUGCUGGUCUUCAGUAAUGACAACACGACCCUGGAGCACCCAGCUGCUCUCCUGGUCUCUGAUGAAACUGUGGAACUGUGGUCCUAGCCUCGAAUCUGGCCAGCAGAACACCUGAUUUGGCAACAGUCAUGAAAUCUGCUGUGGUUAUUACAGCACGGAGAGGGAGUAAUUGUUCAUUUCCAGGGUGUUGGAGCCACUUUCUCCCUCCUCUUAGGCUUGAGAUCCAGCAUGGGUGUACUCCAAAAAUCAUUCCUUUCUGUGU